GCCCUCGUCUUCCCGCGGCCGGUGGCCUGGAAGGCCGGAGAGGCCCAGCUUGUGCUUUGGUGCCUCGCUCCCGCCUCUCGGGCGUUCUCUACUGGGGCAGGGGAGCAGCUUUAUUUCUUGGGGCACACAGGCUGCAAUUGUAGAGUUAGAACCUCAUUGGGAUCCUUGAGUGGGGGUGGAGGCCAGAAAAAUAGGAACCCGAGGAUAUUGGGGGCUAGGGCGGAGAGGCCGAGGAAUAGUGGUGUGGAUGAGACUCCUGGGAGCGGGGCGCCGGCUACUAGGGAAAUGGGAAGGGAUGUGAAGAUUUCUGUGGGAACGGUGUAUCCAACUUGCUUUUCUCAACAGUUUACUAAAUACUGAACAUUAAUGCGUGUGAUUUUUAAAAAAUCCGUAGGUUGUGGUUUAAGUUUUGAUUUAACAUAUCGACCCUUUAAAUGACCUUUUCACCUUUAUACUUUAAGGGAGCUACAUGCACAUUUCUCUUGUGCAGUGGUCUGUCAUUGUUAUAAACAGACUAAGAAAUUUAUUUGAAAUGCUUUAUACUGUAGGCUCUCCAUUUGUCAGCAUAGUCUCCAUCUUAACCAUCCGUCUAUAGUCAAGUUAUUUUUGUUACACUUGUUUUUCCUUUGGAAAAUAAGUUCAUUCAUGCACCUGUUAAAUUGCUGAAAUAGUUGUGCACGCAGCAUUCUCUUACAAGCGGCAGCCUGCUUGUGUUUUCUAUACAAUUUUUAAAAUUCUAAACUUUUCAUUUAGAAAAACUGUUUCUGGGUUUUUUUGUUUGUUUGUUUGAGACGGAGUCUCUCUCUGUUGCCCAGGCUGGAGUGCAGUGGCGCGAUCUCGGCUCACUGCAACCUCCGCCUCCCGGGUUCAAACGAUUCUCCUGCCUCUGCCUCUCGAGUAGCUAGGACUACAGGCGCGUGCCACCACGCCAGGUUAAUUUUUUGUAUUUUUAAUAGAGACGGGAUUUCACCGUGUUAGUCAGGAUGGUCUCGAUCUCCUGACCUCGUGAUCCGCCCGCCUCGGCCUCCCAAAGUGCUGGGAUUACAGGCGUGAGCCACUAUUUCUGGGUUAUUUUGAGAAGCUUAUAUUUUAUUUUCAUUUUGGGCGGGCGUCAUGACAGGGAGAUAGAAGAACUCUCCAACUUCCAGUGCCUUCUUCCUUAAUUAUUAUCCUGGCAUCCGCAUCUUAGAUUAAUUUAGCAGAUAUUAAUACAACAUCUGUAACAAGAACUAUUCUCAGUGUUUGGAGGUACAAGGGUGAAAAAGAACAUGUGUCGGGGAUCUUACCCCAUUUUAAUGGAACUAUUUUCUCUUAAGCCAAUUCGUAUUUCAUCUGAAACAAUAGAAUAGACAUCAUUAACAUUUAAUAAUACCUCAGUCAUGUACUUCAUCCAUCAUAUUCUUAUGAAACAAAUCAUGCCAUGUGGAAUCGUAUGUAAAACUGGGCCACGUGGAAGAAUUUCAACAGACUUGGAUUAUCAAAAUGUUUUUAUAACAUUAAUCUUUUAAAUGCAUAGUCUCGGUCGGUCGUGGUGGCUCAUUCCUGUAAUCCUAGCACUUUCGGAGGCCAAAGCGGGCGGAUCACGAGGUCAGGAGAUCGAGACCAUCCUGACUAACAGUUGAGGCCAGGCAUUGAGGACCAGCCUGGCCAACGUAGCGAAACCUCAUUUCUACUAAAAAUACAAAAAAAAUUAGCUGGGCCUGGUGGUGGGCGCCUCUAAUCCCAGCUGUUCGGGAGGCUGAGGCAGGAGAAUCGUUUCAACCCAAGAGGGGGAGGUUGCAGUGGGCCGAGAUUGGGCCACUGCACUCCAGCCUGGGCGACAGAGCUAGACUCUGUCUCAAAAAUUAAUAAUAAUAAUCUCCGGUGAUCAUUAACACUUAGACCUAUACUUGACAAUAAUUAUUUUAUUAAUCAUAAGAUAUCAAAGAGAUGUUUAUGCUUUUAUGCUUUGGGUAUUUUCUGGAAUCUUUAACAAGAAACCACCAGCAUGCUAAAGUUUCUUGCAGAACAUAAAUUAUUAGGAAACAUUAAAAAUGUGGCCAAGACAGCUAACAAGGACCACUUGGUUACAGCCUAUAACCAUCUUUUUGAAACUAAGCGUUUUAAGGGUACUGAAAGUAUAAGUAAAGUGUCUGAGCAAGUAAAAAAUGUGAAGCUUAAUGAAGAUAAACCCAAAGAAACCAAGUCUGAAGAGACCCUGGAUGAGGGUCCACCAAAAUAUACUAAAUCUGUUCUGAAAAAGGGAGAUAAAACCAACUUUCCCAAAAAGGGAGAUGUUGUUCACUGCUGGUAUACAGGAACACUACAAGAUGGGACUGUUUUUGAUACUAAUAUUCAAACAAGUGCAAAGAAGAAGAAAAAUGCCAAGCCUUUAAGUUUUAAGGUCGGAGUAGGCAAAGUUAUCAGAGGAUGGGAUGAAGCUCUCUUGACUAUGAGUAAAGGAGAAAAGGCUCGACUGGAGAUUGAACCAGAAUGGGCUUACGGAAAGAAAGGACAGCCUGAUGCCAAAAUUCCACCAAAUGCAAAACUCACUUUUGAAGUGGAAUUAGUGGAUAUUGAUUGAAAUAGCAGUGCUUCAGCUCUAAGGAUAUUAGCAACAAUGAUAAAACUUGGCCUUGAAGAAAUUUACACAACUAGUUAGAACUUGUUACUAUUGUAAAGGAAGAGUCAACUGGAAAAUUCAAGGAGUUAAUAAAAUUUGUUUACUUGGUCCCAGCUUUUGAGAGAUAAAUCCCUUAUGAAUCCCUGGUCUAAAAUACUUUCCUACAGCUGUGUAAAAUACUGGUCAAGGAGAACUUUUUCCUUUUACCUCAUGUUGUAAACUUAAGUGGCUCAAUAAAAAUUGAUCCACUGUCUUGAUCUGACUGUGAUUUGUUUGGUGUUAAUAUAUUAUUGUUCUGAUUAGGGAAUUGGAACUAAGGACCUCAUCAAACCAGGGAGUAACUCCCAGUAAAAUUAUCUGGACAGAUUGCCUGUAUAAUGAGAAGGCAAAAGCAUAAGGCUUGAGGGGAAACAAAAUGCUAAAAGCAGAAAAAUCUUGGCAGGAAGAUCAAGACCUGAAUUUAGAAAAGGUGUACUUCAAAACCAAUGAGCCACUAAUAAAGGUGAACAUAAGGUUAAUAUUACUAAUUGAUCCCCCCAAAAUAAAUUCAUAAACAAUUA